GUAGCGGGUGCAGUCCAGCUGCUCUGGACGCUGAGGCCCCGGCUUCUCUUGCUGGGGUGUCGAUUCGGGAGGGCUGAGGGCGCGGCCGAGAGAACGGGGCGGUCACCGCCGCCGUGGCCCGCGCGUCCCGCGCUCUCCUUGCAGUGCAGGCCCCAGCCGCUCUCGGGCGCGGCGUGGGGGAGGCGGCCCUGCAGGUGCGUACCCGGGGUCCGACACGUGCGGGGCUUCCUGCGAGCUGAGUCCCCGCUGCGCGUCUUCAGGCCUUUGUAAGUUGUCAAAUUUCCCACCGGCCCAGCUCAUCGAGCUUCUUCCCAGCUGUGAACAGGAGGGCCUGUUCCCUAAUUCUUGCCGAAAUUGUUCCAACUGCUGGUGUUCUGCAAGAUGGAGCCAGGAGGAGAGCCCACAGGUGCUAAAGAGAGCAGUACCCUGAUGGAGUCCCUUGCAGCUGUGAAGGCUGCUUUCCUGGCGCAGGCCCCGAGUGGCAGCCGGUCAGCCGAGGUGCAGGCAGCUCAGAGCACGGAGCCUGCCGCAGAGGCAGGCGCUCCCGAGGGAGAGGGCCACAGAGGGGGGCCUCCCCGGGCGUUGGGGUCUCUUGGCCUUUGUGAAAACCAGGAAGCCAGAGAGAGGCCCGGAGGUUCCCCUCGAGGCCCGGUCACUUCUGAGAAAACUGGAGGACAGAGUGGCCUCGAGUCAGACGUCCCUCCGAACGCAGGCCCCGGCGCAGAGGGCGGGGGCAGCUGGAAGGGGCGGCCUUUCCCGUGCGGCGCCUGUGGCCGCAGCUUCAAGUGCUCCUCGGACGCGGCAAAGCACCGGAGCAUCCACUCGGGGGAGAAACCGUACGAGUGCAGCGACUGCGGGAAGGCCUUCAUCCACAGCUCGCACGUGGUCCGGCACCAGCGGGCGCACAGCGGGGAGAGGCCCUACGCGUGCGCCGAGUGCGGCAAGGCCUUCGGCCAGAGCUUCAACCUCCUCCGGCACCAGCGCGUGCACACGGGCGAGAAGCCCUACGCGUGCGCCGACUGCGGCAAGGCCUUCGGCCAGAGGUCGGACGCCGCCAAGCACCGCCGCACCCACACCGGGGAGAGGCUGUACGCGUGCGGCGAGUGCGGGAAGCGCUUCCUGCACAGCUCGAACGUGGUCCGGCACCGGCGGACCCACCACGGGGAGAACCCGUACGAGUGCCGGGAGUGCGGCCAGGCCUUCAGCCAGAGCUCCAACCUCCUCCAGCACCAGCGCGUGCACACGGGGGAGCGGCCCUUCGCCUGCCAGGACUGCGGCCGCGCCUUCAGCCGCAGCUCCUUCCUCCGCGAGCACCGCCGCAUCCACACCGGGGAGAAGCCCCACCAGUGCGGCCACUGCGGGCGCGCGUUCCGGGCGCUGUCGGGCUUCUUCCGGCACCAGCGACUCCACACGGGCGAGAAGCCGUUCCGCUGCACCGAGUGCGGCCGCGCCUUCCGCCUGAGCUUCCACCUCAUCCAGCACCGGCGGGUGCAUGGCGCCGAGUGAGCCGGGGCUGCGGCGGAAGAGAUGCCGGCGGCCUGGUGGGCGCGAGGCCGAGGCCGGGGGAGGCUCCUGUCCGCCCCGUGCGCGGUGAGGAAGUAACAGCCGGCUGCGCGCCUGGUUCUCGGGUUGCGAAAGCCUCGCCAGGCCUGCAUCCGCCUUGGCUUGGGAGCAAUCAGGAGAGACAGGGCUCGGGGAAGGCGAGCGCUGCCCGCGGGAGGCGAUUCCCAGAGGCGGGGAGGUCUCAGGGGUCUGUCCCGGGCCGGCCGCCCGCCUCUGAGACUCCCCGCCUCCCACGGUCAGCUGCUGCGGGGCAGUGGCCGGUGAUUGAAUCGGUCAUUCCUCCGCAACCAGGCCUCCAUCAAAACCCUGCAUGAGAUGAGGGCCUCGGGCUUCGGGUUGGUGAAGGCGGGGUGGGGGGGCAGUUAGGAAGGGGGCGCCCAGACAGGGCAUGGAAGCCUCGCGUCCUCCCCCGUACCUUGCGGGUCGGUGGUUCAUCCAUGUAUUUCAACGCCUUUUCACAGCCGGUUCAUAUGGUCCCGACUUCUGUGUGCUUAGAAAAUUAUGGAACUUGGCCGGGUGCGGUGGCUCCCGCCUGUAAUCCUAGCACUUUGGGAGGCCGAGGCGGGCGGAUCACACGGUCAAGAGAUCAAGACCAUCCUGGCCAACAUGGCAAAACCCCCAUCUCGACUAAAAAUACAAAAAAUUAAUUGGGCGUGGUGGCGUGCGCCUGUAAUCUCAGCUACUUGGGAGCCUGGGGCAGGAGAAUCACUUGAACCUGGGAGGCGGAGGUUGCAGUGAGCGGAGAUCUGGGCACUGUACUUUAGCCUGGGCGACAGAGAGACCCAUCUCAAAAAAAAAAUUGGAACCUGAGAAGGGGGUCGUGGGGUCCCCGGGGCCCACCGUCUGCACUUGGCAUCUGAAGUCGGGGUGGUCUUGUGGGACUGACCCCUUACCCUGUGGGUUCUGCACUAGCUCCGGGCAAUUGGUGACAGAAUCGAGUUAAAUUGUAGGACAUCGCGUUGGUGUCUGAGAGGGAGUUGGAGAGCUGGUUGGUGUGGAGGGAAAGGCUUACACACAUGUGAUUUCAGAAGCGUUCUGUGGGUAGAGGAAUCGUUUUCUCUUUGAGACUGUUAUGAGUAUGUACAAAUGUUAUUUCCUGUAAAAUAUUUUCAUUUUUUAAAAUGUUAUUUUCUAGAUAGAAAAGUAGAAGUGUCUCUUUGGGGAGCGUUUUUGGGGGCGUAUAGUAAAGCUCUGUCAUCAUGAAUUAAGCGAGGUGGGCUUUGAGUUUCUUGGGAUGACAGGGAAAUGUGAGCCGCCUACUGGCCGUGAGCCCCUGGGGUGCGGUUGCAGGAUUCGCCCAUCCUGGUCUGGGUGUGGCUUGUGACCACCUCCUGCAGUUCUCUGCCCAGGUAAGGACUAAUUGGGAAGAAUUCUGGGUCCUGAGCUGGCUGCCGCUUCCAAGACAGUCGCUUUGAGGGCUCUUGGCACCGAUUUUGUUAAAAUGCAUGAGCUUAGGGUUGUGCAGCCUGUAGGGGCAGGGGUGGUCUCAGAAUGGAUUUGGUGGCCCCACCGUUAAUUAAGCUCCUGACCCCUGGGCCGGUGGUGAGGUGGGAAGAUGAGCCUGUGUCUCCCAUGCUGAGCCAAGAUCCUCAGGUACCAGUAGCGGUCAAAGCACCUGCUCCCUGAAGGAAGCUUACCUGGCUUAGCCUCAUUCCUGCUCGUAAGUCAGGCAUUCAGCUUGCAAAGAUCCCCAAGCACACAAGGAGAGUCAGCUGACUGAGGGCCAACAGAAACAGCAGGCAGCCGCUGUCAGCCACAAAGAAACGCAGAUCCUGAAACUGUCAUCAUACAGGUGAGAGGAUAGUUAUGUGUGAGGUGUUCAAAGAAGUCGCGCAGUCAGUGAUGAGAAAGCUGUAGGGUACAUACUGUCACGCAUGAAUAGGCAGGACUCCUUAAAGAACUUUUGGAAAUGAAAAACAGGCCAGGUGCAGUGGUUCAUGCCUAUAAUCCCAACACUUUGGGAGGCCUAAGGGGGAGGAUCACUUGAGCCUAGGAGUUCAAGACCAGCCUAGGCAACAUAGGGCUGGGCACGGUGGCUCACGCCUGUAAUUCCAGCACUUUGGGAGGCUGAGGCAGUGGAUCACCUGAGGUCAGGAGUUUGAGACCACCCUGGCCAACAUGGCAAAACCCCAUUUCUACUAAAAAUACAAAAUUAGCUGGGCAUGGUGGCCCACACCUGUAAUCCCAGCUACUCGGGCAGCUGAGGCAGGAGAAUCCCUUGAACCUGGGAGGCAGAAGAUGCAGUGAGCCGAGAUCACGCCAUUGCACUCCAGCCUGGGCAAAAAGAGCAAAACUCCAUCUUAAAAAAAUAAAUAAAUAAAGGAAAAUGAGCCGAGUGAUGGUCUUAGAUAUAAGAUGGAAUGGCAAGCAAAUAAAAUUAUAAAUAUGAAUACAUAUGUAUAUAUAAAAGAAUAGUGUCAACUAAAAUACUAGACAACAAUAGCAUGUAAAUUAGAAGGGACAGAAAUGUUCUAAGACCCUCCGGUUGUUGGGAAGAGGGUGUAAGAUAGUGUUUAAUUUGACUUUGAUAAGUUAAAUGUGCAUAGUGUAAUUUAAUGUUAAUUACUAAAAGAGUGUAACCAGUCUAUACAUCUCUAAUCCAAUAAAAAGAAUAAAACACUGUGAUUUAAAAUGUAGUCCCAGCUGCUUGGGAGACUGAGGCAGGAGGAUCUCGGCUUGGAUCCUCAGACCAGGAGUUUGAGGCAGCAGUGAGCUACGAUUGUGCCGCUGCACUCCAGACUGGACAACACAGUGAGAGCCCAUAAAAUAAAUAAAUGAACUGAACACAAACUUCUGUCAAUUAAAAAAUAAGAACGAAAUCAGGCUGGGCCUGAGCGCUGUGGCUCACACCUGUAAUCCCAGCACUUUGGAGGCCAAGGUGGGUGGAUCGCUUAAGCCCAGGAGUUCGAAACCAGCCUGGGCAACAUAGGGAGAACCUGUCUCUACAAAAAAUACAGUAAGUAAGCCUAUAGUUCCAGCCACCCAGGAGGCUGAGGUGGGAGGAUCACCUGAGCCUGGGAGCUCGAGACUGCAGUGAGCUGUAGUCAUACCACUACACUCCAGCCUGGGCAAAAGAGUGAGACCCUCUCUCAAAA